CCCACAGGGGAGAUGGUCAGGCCAGUGUGGGGGCUAAUGAAUAAAUGCUACACUGUGCCCACUCAGGUGGGUAAGGGCUGGCACUCCUCUUCCCCUGGAGUGGGGCGGCUGUGCUGGCACCCUUGGCAGACACAGUAAGGGGGACUGCACCUGGAAAGGAUGGGCCAGUCGGGGCAGGACUACUCAUCACUCAUAGUGUGGGUGUCAGGGUUGUGUCACCCCUCCCACCUCCCUCUGCAGAGACGCAAAGUCAAGAGUAGGAAGAAGCCAACCUCUGAGGUCACGACCCCCAGGAGACCUGGAGGACUGAAUGCUGCUGCCCCCAAGGAGGAGGCUGCCGUCUUAUCCCAGGAGGGAGAGCAGGAAAAUAAAAAGGUUCAAAAGGAAGUUGCUGCGUAUCCAUCUGAGGCCUCUGAGGACAGCAAAGAGCAAAGGCCCUGGGACCGGGUCUACGUGCCCAUGACAGAGCUCUGGCUGGACUGGUUCUGAGCCUCUAACACCCCCAAGACUCAGAACCGUGAAGAAAAUCUUUCCAAUAAAUCCAAGAGUUGCUGCUGCUAUA